AAAACUUACAGAGCAGCAGCCUCGAAGAGAGCAAAGAGGGAAGCGUGGGCAUCUGGGACCUCCAGAGACUUGAGCUGGUGGACGGAGGAGAGGAGACAUUUGAAAGGAGAUCCUAGUCAUUCUCUACAACACAGUUCAAACAUCGCUGCCUCAAGGAAACCCUGCCUCACCACAUCAUCAGCCCUCAGCUUCCGUCCCAGCCCCGGCCAAGUGAUCUUCCUCUCUGUUCCCAUGACUCUGGGAAAUCAGCCUUUGCCAUCAGAAUGUCUGACCCUAAGCCUACAACAGAUUAAAGUUUGUAACAGUCUCAAAGGCAAAGCAGAAGCCCGCAUUUCCCCUGAAGUGUUAAUGGGAAGUCCUCCAACAAAAGCCAAGAUCUCAUUUAUUUUCUGCCUUGUUUACUAAAGAAUUACUUUCUUCAUUUAGGUUCCUUCUUCCUUUCUCUUCUCAGCAUCCUUAAAACCACAGUGUUUGUCAAAUAUAUUUAACCAUGGUUUGUGGGGGCUUUUUGUUUUUUGCUGUAACAUAUUUCUGCAAGACAUUCUUUUUGAAAUGUUGAAAGACAGUGGUGACUGAGCCUGCCAGAUUAUCUGGGACAUAAGCUGGAACUGGAUCUAGUACCUGUGAACAAGUGUAUUCUGACUUGAUAUUGACAAAUAAGGAAAAGUUAUUACUGGAUGCAAGUUCUGGGAAGACUAUAGCAGUAUCUGUCUCUGCUCUUGGAGAUUGGAAUGCAGAACUCUGCAAGGAGGAACAUUCUAUCUCCCUGUCAUAAAGAGUCAUUAGCAACCACCUGGUGCAGGUCACAAGCAGGGAGAGGAAAGACUGCAGAGUCUUUCGUUCUUUCUGGUGCAGCUUAACUGAUUUGAAGAAGCCGAAGAAGAAAAUCCAGUAGCACGGUUAAGACUUUAGCCAUGGCAUCUGUAUCAUACCAAAAGCCAACAUCUACUACUGUGGGAAAACAAAUGAUUUUUACAGGUCCAGACUACAUAAAGGAUUAUUUACCCAAAAUUCAUCAGCACACCUCCUAUGUAGGAGAACAGCAUCUGGCGUUAGAAAAAACUGGAGAUCUCAGAUAUUUAUGGAGGCCUGCCUCAAAUAGAAGCUUGCCAGCAAAAUAUAAACAUGAGUACGUCAGUGAAAUUGGUUGGAGAAUACCACAGUAUAAUUUUAUCAACAAAUCAAGACUGGGGAGUGGCUUUCAUAUCAAGUAUGAAGAACUAAGUCAAGCUUCUCUUGAUUCAAUAACCCACAGAUAUCAAAACCCAUGGCAACCAAAACCUCAUGUCCUGGAUAUGCAAGGAAAACAGAGUCGCGCUUCUUUUGCCUGGCAUAUGAGUGCUUUCGAGGACACUGAUCAGAGAAAUUCCAAAUGGGCUAUUCUUGUUAGGCAGUGUAAGUCAUCAUUGCCAAGAGCUUCCAAACCACCUAAGCUGCCGAAGCUACCAAAAAAGGAAAAGAAAAGGAAACAUUAACCUCUAAAUCAGCAUAACUCAACCUGCUUUUAGAAGGAGAAACUGCCUACUACUGUAUAACAAAAAAUAAGAUCAUAAUAAUCCACAAGUGCUUCUCAUAUUGCCCCAGGACAGAUGUCUUGCAAGAGUACGCUUCAGCUUAAAGCCCAAAUAAACAGUUUGGAAAAAAGGUGUUGUCAGUCUUUGCAACCAUUAAUAUUGUUUCAUGAAACUAAUUGUUAUUGACUAUCAUACUAAUAGUAGCUGUUUACUGAGUGCUUAUAACAUCUAACACUAUUCCAAGUGCUUUACAUUCAUUCUCUAAUAUAAUUUCAUAACCAUAGGAGAUAGGUUCUAUUAUUUCCCCAGCUUUGCAGAUAAGGAAAUUAAGGCUUUGAAAGAGUACAUGGUUAGGAAGUAGCAGAACUUGGAUUUGACCCCAGGUUAUGGGGCUCUAAAGCUAACAUAUAUGGCUUUUAAAGUAUUUUAUAAUAUUGGCAUGGUGCUUUAGCAGUAAAAAGCAGUUAUAUCCCUAAUUUUCAGAAGAUUCUCACAGCACCCUUGUUGAACAGGUACUAUCUUUCUUUUAC